GCUUCCGGCGGCGCCUCAGGUCGCGGGGCGCCUAGGCCUGGGUUGUCCUUUGCAUCUGCACGUGUUCGCAGUCGUUUCCGCGAUGCUGCCUCUGCUGCGCUGCGUGCCCCGUGUGCUGGGCUCCUCCGUCGCCGGCCUCCGCGCUGCCGCGCCCGCCUCGCCUUUCCGGCAGCUCCUGCAGCCGGCACCCCGGCUGUGCACCCGGCCCUUCGGGCUGCUCAGCGUGCGCGCAGGUUCCGAGCGGCGGCCGGGCCUCCUGCGGCCUCGCGGACCCUGCGCCUGUGGCUGUGGCUGCGGCUCGCUGCACACCGACGGAGACAAAGCUUUUGUUGAUUUCCUGAGUGAUGAAAUUAAGGAGGAAAGAAAAAUUCAGAAGCAUAAAACCCUCCCUAAGAUGUCUGGAGGUUGGGAGCUGGAACUGAAUGGGACAGAAGCGAAAUUAGUGCGGAAAGUUGCCGGGGAAAAAAUCACGGUCACUUUCAACAUUAACAACAGCAUCCCACCAACAUUUGAUGGUGAGGAGGAACCCUCGCAAGGGCAGAAGGUUGAAGAACAGGAGCCUGAACUGACAUCAACUCCCAAUUUCGUGGUUGAAGUUAUAAAGAAUGAUGAUGGCAAGAAGGCCCUUGUGUUGGACUGUCAUUAUCCAGAGGAUGAGGUUGGACAAGAAGACGAGGCUGAGAGUGACAUCUUCUCUAUCAGGGAAGUUAGCUUUCAGUCCACUGGCGAGUCUGAAUGGAAGGAUACUAAUUAUACACUCAACACAGAUUCCUUGGACUGGGCCUUAUAUGACCACCUAAUGGAUUUCCUUGCCGACCGAGGGGUGGACAACACUUUUGCAGAUGAGCUGGUGGAGCUCAGCACAGCCCUGGAGCACCAGGAGUACAUUACUUUUCUUGAAGACCUCAAGAGUUUUGUCAAGAGCCAGUAGAGCAGACAGAUGCUGAAAGCCAUAGUUUCAUGGCAGGCUUUGGCCAGUGAACAAAUCCUACUCUGAAGCUAGACAUGUGCUUUGAAAUGAUUAUCAUCCUAAUAUCAUGGGGGAAAAAAUACCAAAUUUAAAUUAUAUGUUUUGUGUUCUCAUUUAUUAUCAUUUUUUUCUGUACAAAUCUAUUAUUUCUAGAUUUUUGUAUAACAUGAUAGACAUAAAAUUGGUUUAUCUCCUCCAA